GAAGUCGGCGCCGGAACUGCCCUAAUGGAAACCAGCCGCCGGGCGCUCCGGGAGGGCUCAGGCCGACCCCGGGGUCCAUUAGAGGCGCCCCAGGCCGAGGGAGCCCGCGGCGGCUGGAAGGACAUGAAAGCUAUGUGACCUUCUGCCAGCUGGAGGAUGAGGCUGCCUUCACAUGCAGCGCCGACUGCACCAUCAGGAGGUGGGACGUGCUGACCGGGCAGUGUCUGCAGGUGUACCGAGGACACACGUCCAUCGUGAACAGGAUCCUGGUUGCCAACAACCAGCUCUUCAGCAGCUCCUAUGACCGGACAGCUCGGGUCUGGAGUGUGGACAAGGGGCAGAUGUCCCGGGAGUUCCGGGGCCACCGCAACUGCGUGCUGACCCUAGCCUACUCUGCCCCGUGGGACCUCCCCAGCACUCCCUGCGCGGAGGAGGCCGCGGCCGGGGGGCUUCUGGUGACCGGCAGCACAGAUGGCACAGCCAAGGUGUGGCAGGUGGCCAGCGGCUGCUGCCACCAGACGCUGCGGGGCCACACGGGUGCAGUGCUGUGCCUAGUGCUAGACACGCCCGGCCACACGGCCUUCACAGGCAGCACCGACGCCACCAUCCGUGCCUGGGACAUCCUGAGUGGGGAGCAGCUGCGGGUGUUCCGGGAGCACCGGGGCUCCGUCAUCUGUCUGGAGUGUUCACGGGCAGCGGGGACGCUUGCGCCCGGGCCUUCGACGCGCAGUCUGGAGAGCUGCGGAGGGUGUUCCGGGGCCACACAUUCAUCAUCAACUGCAUCCAGGAGAGAAGCUGCAGGUGACAGUGUCUGCCGUGGAGAGCUCAUCAUCUCGCUGCAGAGAGAAGCACCUGCUGCAGGAGCAGCCCCUUCAAGUGGAGCAGCCCCUUCAAGUGGAGCAGCCCUUUCAGGUAGAGCAGCAUGCGCUUCAUAGUCUUAAUGCAGAAGAUACUUCAUCAGAGACGGCCGGGGCCGCCAGGGAUCACCUGCUAGGUGAUGGGCGGGUCCGCCCUCGGGCGCGGAUGAACAGGUAGGGAUUGCACUGUGGGCAGUAGGAAGGAAAGGACGCAGGCGCUGUAACUCCUCUAGGCCAAACCUCCAAACCCUGGGAACCAAAGUGCCCCCGACCCCCACCCCAGGAAAAUGGGCCUGUUGGGAGGCAAGCAGAUCGGUGCAGGAGAACCCGCAGAAACGGCACCAUGCACUGUUCUCCGGGUGAGACUUAAGCACACACAGACCUCGGGGGUGGCCAGGUCUUGCUGCGUCCCGGAGCCAUUGGGGCCUGUGGCUGCCACAAGGGGCAUACCUACCAGAGAGGACCUUUCCAUCGUGCUGAAGGGACGGUUCCGGUGGCGCAGGCCAGAGAACCGCCUUGAGUGCUGCCUGCGGGCAGUGCUGCCGGCCGGCCCUGAGCCUGCACAGACGUUCACACUGACUCCUGCUUGCCGAAGACACUGCUGCUUGGUGAUGCUGCGCUCUGGCCUGAGCAGCCCCUCACUGACACGUCAGCUCCAGUCCCCACCUUAUCUCCCCACAGCAGAGAAUGGAGCAUGCAUCAAGCCAUCCAGAGAAACCCAGUGGGGCAUGGACCCAAAACACGGGCGCUGCACUCACUUUGCAUUUUUAUAGCAACACACAUUGGGGUAAUUUCUACUUCCAUUGCACAGAGAGCUUUGCGAGAUGUUGAGGACAUAAAGAUGGCCAGAUGUCCAUUUUCGCUCUGGUUUCUGACAGCCUGAGAGACACGGUGAGUGAGAGAGUCUGAUCCCCUGAACCCAGGCCUGGUUCCCUUCCAGCCACACCACUGUCGCCUUGCUAUGAAUGAAGAAACAAGGUGUCUGCUUUUGAUAAAUUGACUGAGGAGGAGUUGGCUAAGGGAGGAAGGACAGGAGCUACCCAUAGGACAUAUGGGCAGGAACACAAGGACAGGGUAAGGCCGUGAUCAGCAUCAAGGACACCUGACCAGUUGUGCACACCAUUGUGCUGGCAUGGGCUGCCCUCACCUGCCUGCUACACGCCCAUGCCCACUCCUGCUCCUCUAAUGGCAUCCAACCUCCCCGCUGUGAUCAGCAAUCAUACCAUCCGCCCCCAUUCUUCUCUCCCCACAACCCGCACCUUCUGGCAGCCCAUGAACAUGUCACACUCAGACUGUCCUGCCCCAAAUACUAUCUUGUUUGUCCCACAUCUGGAAUGUGCUUUUUCCUCUGACUCCCCAAGGAGAACCCUCCCAGGCCCCCUCCUCUGCAACGGCCUCUCCUCCAACCUCAGCACCGUCCUGCCCCCUCCUCUACCGCCUGUCCGGUGGAGCAGGCCCGGCCCAAGUCUCCAUGCCUGGAGGGCAGCCCAUUCUGGACAUAGCGCAUGCCCAGAACUGCCUCCACAGCCGGCUUCCUCUGCGGCUCUCUCUUCACAAGACACGGAAGAGUUUUGGGGCCUGCUGGUGUGGCAUUGCUUCUAUGAUGGCUAAAAACAGCUGGGAAGCUAGAAGACACGCCUGAACCAAGCGCAGGACAGCGAUUUGUUAGCCAAAAGCUUAAAUUCAGGCCCCAAAUCCAAGUGUGGCAUUGUGUCAAAUGAGGCUGAGACUCCGCGUCACCUCAGCUCACCAGGCACUUCUGAGGCAAACCCUGACAGGUACAUUUCAGUCCCCUGCCCAGGAUGCACCCCAGCCCCGCUUGGCGUGCGGCAUCUUUCACAGCAGAUGCCCUCUGCUUCUGAGAUCAUCCUUCCAUCAUCUCCUCACAAAACUCAGUGGAAACAGACAUCCUGCAAUCAAAAUGAAGAGCUAGUCACCCAGACACUUUCAACACCUACAGCUGGGGAGGCUGAGUAAAUUAAUGCAAAAUUAGGGUGACAAUUUUUGAAUAUAUUUCCCACCUUUUAUUUCCAUCGGUAUCAUCCGUUUAAAAAGAAUGACAAGAAGAUUCCCAUCAGUCCAAACUGGACCACCCACACUUUGAAAAAGUUGGAGCAUUUCAGCCGGCUCCGCAUGAUCCAUCCUGUCUUCAGUCAGUGCCUUCUGGAAGGGAGGGAAAGUCUUGGAUGCACCUGGCACUCAAUCCACUCGGCACCUGGCUGCUGCUGUGGUCCUGGGGCUGGAAGGAACUCCCACUGGGCACACAUCUACAGAGGAGUGCGUGGCGCAGUGAGGACGGUUACUGCUGGAGCCGACACACAGCGAACUACAUACUUUUAGAAAGAGCCUCUGUCACAUGGCUAGAACAACAACAACAACAAAGAAAACCCACAAAAAACCUGGAGAAAAUAUAUCUAAAUCUCUGAUAGGUCUCUUAGCUAGCAGUGAGUUCAGUAUGACAGCACAGAGUCUAAAAAUAUUAAUUAAAAAUAAAUUGCUUUGGUUAGCAUUUAAACCUUUCCCAUUCAAUAGAAGAUUUCUGUAAUGAGGAAUGCUGAAUAUAUAUAAAGCCUGACACUCAAUCUUGAAUUUCGGGGGCGUAUUUUACUGAACUAAGAGCAUAAAACACUGGCGUCCCAGGCUGAAGCCAUUUGCUGCGACCUGGUGUGGCCCCCAAGGCCAGCGCCUCAUCGUUAUGCCCCACAGCACUUGGAAGGAAGACUUAAAGGACGAUUUGAGGGGCGGGGAAAGGGUGGCACAGGAACCCAUGUGGCACCCUGGCAGAGAUGGCAGCGUGGGAAGCAGGAAGGUCAGGGCAGUGGGUGCAGGAGGCAGGCAAGCUGGGCAGAUGGAGCCACAGCUGGAGAGGAAGCGGUCGGGACACCCUUCCCAGGACCCUGCCCUGGACACCUUCCCCAGGACCCCUGUUCUACAGGACCCCUGUUCCUUCCUGUUUCGGGGUAAAACACCAAGCUGGGGAAGGGGUUAGGGACGCAGACCUGGGAGGCAGAUGGAACGGCCUGCGCCAGGCCAGAGGAAGCUUCUUCCCCGAGACCACGCAUGAAGGCCCUGGGACCCCUCCUGGACUUGUCCCCUGCCCACCCCCUCCUACACCCAAAGAGGACUUGUAAUUCAGAUAAAAAGUAAGAACAGAAAGAGCUGCAUUAGCCUUUUCAUAAUGAUAGCAUUUAUAAGCAGAAAAUUAGCGCUAUUUCUGUUCAUUAUUUAGUUUUUCUUUGUUGCUGACUUCCUAUUUUCUACAUAGGAUAGGUACUCUGCAAUAAUAAUUUCUUCAUCUUCCAGAGUUGAGUCAAGAUAGUCUUCCUCAUGCUCUGGAAUGUCUUCCAGUAUCUCAUUGACGGCCUCUGUCUCCAUGUCUUCGUCUGUUGAGGCACUAGAGGUUCCUACAAUAAAAUACCGCAGGAGUAAGUGAAUUAUGUGAGGAUUGUCCUGGGGACACUGCACGACCACAGUCAACCUCAGACUGUGCCUCUUGCUGGCCACACUGUCCAGGUGGCCGGCCCGGUGACGUCAGGGGACGCCCCCUCAGUCUCCACAUCUGCCGUGGCUUAGGGCCACAUCUGUUGGCUUCUGAAGACACUUUGCUCUCAAUGCGGCCCUCAAAGACCUCAGACCUACCUGCGGAGUCAGAAGGGGACGUGGCUGGCGGGGACAAAGAGUCUUCUGGCGACAGCGGCAGCUCGGGAGGCAGGCUUCCUCCGUUGUGAGCAAGGGUCUGGGCGGCCAGCUGGACGUUGCCUCUGAACACUCUCAGCGCAGCUUCGGCCACGAGUGCAUCAAAACCCAUGUACACCAACUAGGGGAGAGCGCAGGGGUCACAGCAUCAGCCCCUGGCGCCUCUUCUGCCACCCCCGUCAGCCAUACGAGUGGACAGCCGACUCUCAUGUUUAAGAGCUCCCGGCGUGUGCACCAUGGCCCUUUGUGCACAAGUCAUGCUUCUGUGCAAUGUGAGCGUAGAGCAACCUGGAAGGGGGCUUGGAAGACUCAAGUCGGGUGCGUCAGGGAGCAGCCAUCUCAGGACAGGCAGUGACCUCGGGCUGAGAGCAGGGCGCCACACCAGCCUCACCACGAGCACCGCGAGGUCAGUGGCCACAGCAUACAGGCGUGCUAACGCGUGUAGGGGCACAAAUGUGGACAGAGCCGUCACUUGGGAUACAAAGCUGGAUGGGUUUCCCAGGUCACAGUGCCAUCCUUUUAGGUCACAGGCAGAGAAAUGAGGCUGAUGCAAACAGUGGUGCAUAGACAAAGGCAGCAAACCUAAAGAGAACUUCCUGACACUUCCCCAGUUUUCCUGCUUUCCAAGGAGGCCUCCCCUGCCCUCUGUUACUGCGUGGGUGGCCUCUGAGGUGGGCAGGUUACACCUGGAGCCUGGGAGCCAAGGUUUCAGCACGGACUCCCCCAGUCCUGCUGCCUGAUUCACCCGGGUUACCCCAAGCAACCCCACCCGAGGCUGUCCAAGCUGAGGGCACAAAGGCCUGUCACUCACUCGGUCAAUGUUUUCCUGGGAAGGACUUUCUUGACGGUUGUCGGUUUCAGGAUUGGAAUCAUUUAACCACCACAUCUGAGGAUUGCUGAGCAGAAUCUAAAACACACAGGAACACCCUUUACCCAUCACUAAGAACUCUUCACACAUUCAGACAGGCGCUGCACCCUGCCAUGUGCUAGGCAGACCCCGCCGUCCUCUGCUGCUAUGAGGCAGAGAAAGGGGCUCCCACUCAGGCUGGUGUUCACAGAAGGCUUCCAGCCAGAGACCAGGACAGCUGGGGUUUGAAGGAGGAGCAAGACUAGUCAGGGAAAAGAUCCCUUCUGUUAGAGCAGGAAGGGAUGGAGAGCAGGUGGAAGCAGCAUCCAAGAAAACAGGUUUUGUCAGAGCUACAGACAGAAAGGUCUCAAGCAGCUCAGGGCUGCCUGAUUGAUCUUUGAAAGCGUCAUGCCCUCUAGACUUAAAAUGUCAGGCAGGUAGUAGGGUUAUUUUGACCCUUGAUUUCUUCAUCACACAAUACUUAAUCUUCAAAGACCCUGUGGAGACUUUCCUUUCCAACACUCAGUACUUCCAUUUUGACUGGAAGUAUUUUUGUGCCACUCGUAUAAUUCACAUCUAUUUUGAGACCCAUCAGUCCCUUCGAAUAUUCAGAAUUUCCCACCUCUUAAUAUUUCUCCAACACACAAAAAAACGAACUAGAUGAUAUUCAAAUAAAAAUUUAAAAUUUAACGUAUAUGUUAAAUAUACAUGUACAUAGUUACAAAAGUACUGACUUGUGGAGCCUUCCGGGGAACAGGGCAGGGAUAAGAGGCAAAGGCAGGGUGGACUCCCCGUGCCUGCUGCACCCACACCCGCCUCAGCAGGGCAAACGAGGACACCUGCCCUGCACCCCACCCCCUCCAACCCCAUCUCUGUCCCCCCAGCCCCGCCCCCAGCACGUGCACAACCUAAGCCAGCUCCUACCACUCUGCUUCCUGCCCGCCGCGCUGCCCCAGCAUCUGUCUGGACUGCUGCCUCCACACAGCCAGCCCCCUGCCUCCUGUGCACCCCCUCGGGACCCCUCACCACGUGUGCUCUGAGUUUGUCUCUCACUGACCUGCGGGGCCGAGAGGGCAGAGGGUGGUUCCAUGCCAAGCUGCUGAGACGCAGCGCAGCACCUGCCCUACUGAGGAUUCGAUAUGCUUCUCCAACACAGGGAAGGAAGUGGCCCAGGUAAAGUCACUGCUGUCUGGAUCCCAACCUGCUGUCACUCCUGAGGGGUUCUUUGAAAAGCUCUCCCUUUGCCAACAUGUACGAUGGACUAAAUAAAUAAAACUAGAUACUUACAUUUAAAAUUUUAAUGCCAAACAAUUAUACUACAAGUUGAAUUCCCAUUCUCUUUUUUCUGCCGUGGAAACUGCCUGUUUCACUAAACUCUGCUGCACACAGAAACCCUACACAAAGUCCUGGCCUGUGGACUGUGCUGGUGUGGACAGGCACCACGUUUUGGAGCCAGGCCUGGGCCAAGCACUGAGCAUGGGGCCUCACGUGGCCUCACGCAGCCUGUGUCUGGGCUGGAGCCCAGGAGAAACCUGCCCUUCAGAUCCGGAUGACGGGGCAGCCCAUAGGAGUGAGCCCGGGAGGAUGCUGGAGAGCCAUGGAGGGAGCUCUGGGCAGGACCCACUGCUCAGGGACAAGGCCAGAGGCCCCGAGGGAGCUGCUACCUUCAGGGCCUCAUCCAAGUUCCCGCUGGCUGCGUGGAGUACCUGCUGGGCCGCGUGCGUGGAGUAGCCCAUCCCUUUCAGAAACCUGAUGUUCUCGAGGCGGCGUCUUUUCUUCUCUUUUUCCUCCUUCCUUAUUUGGGCCAGUUCCUUUAGGAAAACAGCAAAGUCCCAUCCCAAGUUAGGGACUGAGAUUUCACAGCCUCUCAGUCUGCGCUCUGCAGGAUUCUCCGCAUUUCCAGGCAAAGCCAAAAAACCAAAGCAAAGCACAGGGGGCCCUCUUUCUACCUCUCCUCACCCAGCCAAAUGGCAGAGGUGCCACAGAGGCAGAGGGGUGGUGGAAGUGCUGCUUCUGAGGCAGGCAGUGGAAGUGAGAUGCCCGUGGGGCAGGAAGGAGGUGCCUCGCCAGCCCCGCCAUCCACCAUCCGGCAUCAGGAUGGGCUGCUCGCCAACCCAGCACUCCCACUGCAGAGGUCGCGGGUGUGAGGUGCAUGGAUUCUCUUCUAGGAACCAGGUAGGAACCGGGUAGGAGAGCUUCUGCACGCGGUGGGAAGGCCUUCCAGCCUUCGAUGAAUCGCCCAGGGAUUCAAGUUAAAAUGUGAUGUGGAAUCAGGGGCUCCUGGGCAAUGCCAAAGCUGGUGACCCGCCCCCCACAGCCUGGGGAGCAAGGACUCCAGGGCCUUCUGAGGCCUGUCAUUCCAUUCGGAACCCACAGAGUGCCCAGAGACAAAGGUCAUCUAACCUCUUGGUUCUCAACCCUGUUUCUCAGAGUUGCCUGCUAUUGCUGCAGGAGCGCAGGACGGCUGCAGAGGGUUCUAGUCUCUUCACCUCUCCCACCCAGGGCCAAUCAGGAGAGUUCCCAAUUUAUUUUGUAAACUAGUAUCCCCAUAAAAAUGUCAUUUAAAAAGGGGAUUUUGCUGCUUAAAAACAACAACAACAAAGCAAGUUUGAAAACCAGGAAUUUAAUCCAACCUCAUUAUUUUCCCAACAAGGAGACAGAAAGCUUUCAACAAAGUUAAGUGACUUGCUACAUUCUCCCAGGGAGACCAGCCCCACCAUCAGCAGCAGCGAGGACGGGGGAGAAAACAGACUCCUUCCUUCCAGAGACCUGAUCCUGCCUCCUGCCCAGCCCAGGCAACAGGCGCCUCCCUGCAUUUUCCCCACAGCAGGAAAGCGGCCUCAUCUCUUAGGAAAACAAAAGCAUCAUCAUUGUGGAACCAGACUCCACAGGCCCCACAGUAGGAGCAGGCAGAACAGAGUGGCUGCUGGAAACAUCUCCAGGGAUGAAGACAUCUGUAGACUCAUGGCCUGUCUCUAUCACAGGAGAACCUCCUGGUGUGGCCCUGGAGUGCCCACAGCGCCAGCUCCCUUUGCUUCCCCUUCAGCUGCACCAGGCCUGUCUCAUGCCCCCAUUACGUGCUCUACCUCUCAGUGGCCAGUCUCCCCCAGCUCCAGCCCCGCUGCACAGGGCAGCAGGCUCCGUCAUUCCAGUCACCUACCUGAAAGCCCGCAGCAGCUCCUGACCACCUCCCCACACUGAGGCACCAGCUCCUUAUUCUGCUACUCAGGGCCCCCACUCCCUGGCCCCAACAAUGCUUCGAAACUGACCUUAUCCUGCCACACCACCCCAACCACACAUGCCAGCAGGAGUCUUUCAUACCACUCACAUUUGCACUUUUAUUUACACAUACUCCAUGUAAAAUGCCUUUACUGGCCCCAUCCUCUGCUUUCAAUACAGUUUCUUCCAUUUAUAUUCCAAAAGGCUAAGAAGCGCACCUAACAUCCAAGCACAGAGAAGGACGCUGCCAGCCAGCGGACCUGGGCAUUACCUAACACAGACCUCACACCAACUGGGAGCUUCGAAGAAUACUUCCUUUCAUUACAAAUGUCUUAGUCUGUUUCCUUUUAAUCAUGUAAACACAUGUGAGAACAUUAUUUUCUGAAAUUUCUCUUUAUACUAAGAUGAGUUAGAAAGAUAAAGUAGAUCAAAUCAAUGACAGUGAGUACUGCACUGAAGUGGCUACAGUUAAGUAGAAUCAGAUCUCAAGAGAGAGGCACUGUAUGGUCACAACAAGCUGGGAUGGCCUCUUAGGAAGGCUACGUCUCACGGCCUGGCCAUGCCGAAGCAUGAUCUGUGAGCUCCGUUUCUACAGCUGUUGCUUUUCUCAGAUGAGAAACUGGUCUGUACUCAGGGCCAUAUUGCACAAAAAAUAUAAACUUUUAAUAAUUAUGUAUUAAAGGCUGGGUGCAGUGGCUCACACCUGUAAUCCCAGCACCUUGGGAGGCCAAGGUGGGAGGACUGCUUGAACCCAGGAGUUUUGAGACUGGCCUGGGCAACAUGGUGAGACCCCAUUUCUACAAAAAAAUAAAAAUCAGCCGAGAGCUCUUGGCAGGAGGAUCAUUGGAGCCCGGGAGAUCAAGGUUGCAGUGAGCCAUAAUCACGCCACUGCCCUCCAGCCUGGACAAGAGAGCAAGGCUCUGUCUCAAACAAAAACAUGAACGAAUUGUUUUACAUUCAGCUCAGUCAGAUGCUCAUACCUAGAACGUUGGAACUCCGAGGGCAGCAGAUUUCUCUUGCUCAUCUAAAGCUCCGAUAGGAGCUCACUUUCUGUGGGACAUUGUUUUUGUCUUUCCAGCACCCAUUCUACCCCUCCCUGAGGUGUGGGAGGCUGCUCCAGCUCCCCAGGUGGCCCCUGAAUGGGCUAAGGUGGCAACCCUCUAUCUCUUGCCACAGGCCUGAGCCAGUCUUGGCGUUCCUCCAGCCUCAGUGACAGGUUCAAGGCUGCCCAAUCACAAGAAGCUCAGGAUUUUCCCUGAGGAUUCUGGGACACAGAUUAUGGCCCUUGUUGUGACUGGAUGACACUGAUGACAUGGGGUGGGGGGUGGGGGUAAAAGACAGACCUCAGGUCCUCAGUGACAUCAGUAAGCCACUGAAUGAAUCACCUAACCCUGAGACCUAUCCUACUUCUGGACUUUUUACAAGUAAACGGCCAAUAAAUCCCACCACAUCCCUUGUUUUGAUGUUUAGGCCAUUUUGGGUUUUUUGUUGUUGUUGUUGCUUUCAGCCAAAGGCAUCGUAACUAACAACAUCUGUUGGGUGGAAGAGGGAGAAGGAUCAACUGCACUAUAUACACUGGUUUUUUUAUUUGCAUUUUCUCCAAGGGCUUUUAACUUCAGAAAUGUACAAGUGAUAUGACUCCACUAUACUUUAAAAGACCACCUCUGAGCAACAGCUCUUCCCAUGUGUAAGAUGAGAAGUACCUGUCCUGUGGCCUCUCGGCUGGUCACAGGCAGAAGUGAAUGACAUGAGUGUGACAAUGUUUUAUGAACUAUAGUCUUAUACAGUGAUGAGAACUGUUUUCCAAAUGAUCUCAUUUUAAAACACUAGCUUUCCAGAUGCUAAUAAAAUCUUACUUCAUUCUCAGUAAACUAUCGCAAGAACAAAAAACCAAACACCGCAUAUUCUCACUCACAGGUGGGAAUUGAACAAUGAGAACACGUGGACACAGGAAGGGGGACAUCACACUCUGGGGACUGUUGUGGGGUGGGGGGAGGGGGGAGGGAUAGCUUUAGGAGAUAUACCUAAUGCUAAAUGACGAGUUAAUGGGUGCAGCGCACCAGCAUGGCACAUGUAUACAUAUGUAACUAACCUGCACAUUGUGCACAUGUACCCUAAAACUUAAAAGUAUAAUAAUAAUAAAAUAAAAUUAAAGGAAAAAAUAAAUAAAAAUAAAAAUAAUAAAUUCUUACUGGUAGUGGAGUAAUAGUAAAGCAAUAAAUCAGUAUCAGCAAUGUUCAUUUUUCUGUUAGUACUGAAUUAGACCAUGUAAAACUCAAACACACAGAACUCAACUUUUCAGCUGGUCGCAGUGGCUCACACCUGUGAUCCCAGCACUUUGGGAGGCCAAGGCGGGAGGAUCACUUGAGGUCAGGAGUUCGAGACCAGCCUGGCCAAAUUGGUAAAACCCCAUCUCUACUAAAAAUACAAAAAGUAAAGCUGGGCGUGGUGGUGGGCACCUGUAAUUCCAGCUACUUAGAAGGCUAAGGCAGAAGAAUCACUUGAACCUGGGAGGCAGAGGUUGCAGUGAUCACGCCACUGCACUCCAGCCUGGGUGACAGAGUGAGACUCUGGAAUAAAAAAAAAAAAAAGAACUCAGCUUUUCAAAGUCUCUGCCUUUACCUACUCAUUGACUUCUAUAGCAAGACCCAAAGGACCACGAUUGGACUAGGCAAGAGAGAAAGGUAAUGACCACAGCUGGUGUUGUAAAAGGAGAAACCCUGUGACUGCUCACCACGGAAUGAACCCACGAAUCCACUCCCUCUCUGGCAUCAGGUAGGCAAACAACCACGGGGCUUUCCUGCUCCCAUCCAAAUACCCCUGAGGCUGCUUUUUUCCUUCAGGAUUAUCCUAGUGUUUAGCAAAAAGGGAAACGAGGUAACAUACAUGUGAAGAUUCUAGAGACUUCUAUGGCUGGAGUUUACAGCUAGAAAGGACCUGUGAGAUAAUCUAGUACCAACUUCUUGUUUUGGCAAGAAGAAAAAUGGCUCUCCUGCUAAUAUUCCACCAUGACCGCCCUCUAGACCUCAGUUCUUUCACUGCAGAACAUAUUGGAUAGAAUAAGGAUGCUUCCAACUCCAAAAUUCUAAGGUUUUCUUUAAUGUACUUAAUUGUUUCAAAUGAUUAUAGUUUUUUAACCUGUGCUUUCAUAAUAUAAUACAACUUGUUUCUAUGAUUUGACUUAUGUUUCUAGGCAAGGAUGCAAUCCCCAACUUUAAUAAUGACCUCAUGAAAAAACAAUUUUGUUUUUAAAAUGACUUCCAGAAAUACACUAUGGUGUUAAAGAAAGAGAGAGAGGGGACCGUUUGCCACCACAGCAGGAAACAAAACUAAGGAGACUGCAGCAUGUGAAAAAUGAUCCAAUUGAAAAAGACAAGUUUCGGCCAGGCGCGGUGGCUCACACCUGUAAUCCCAGGACUUUGGGAAACUGAGGUGGGCGCAUCACUUGAGGUCAGGAGUUUGAGAACAGCCUGGCCAACAUGGUGAAACCCCAUCUUUACUAAAAAUACAAAAAUUAGCCAGGUGUGGUGGCACACACCUGUAAUCCCAGCUACUCAGGAGGCUGAGGCACGAGAAUUGCUUGAACCCGGGAGGCGGAGCUUGCAGUGAGCCAAGAUCGUGCCACUGCACUCCAGCCUGGAUGACAAAGUGAGACUCUGUCUCAAGAAAAAAAAAAGGACAAGUUUCUCCUUCCUUCCCAAUCUGGAGUAAUAAAGAGUUCCUGGUUAUUAACA